AGCGUAUUUACAAAGGAGCCUCCUCCGCCAGCCCGUGCCACCGCUGCUAAUGAGAGCAGUCAUUAAGUAAAUGAGACGUCGCCUUUAGCUGGCUUAGGAGUUCGCACACUAAGGGGAGAAGAUAUUUAAUUGAAACCCGCACGCAGGCUUCCCCACAUGUGACCGCUGUACGGGAGGCAGCUGCCUUCCCUCUCCUCCCCCAGUCCACCCUGCACCCCCCAUGUAAAUUUCAUGAUUGCUUUCCGUGAUGUCAUUUUGAAAGAGGACAGACAAUAGCUGUGGGGAAAGAAAAUGAGUUCCGAGGUGAGCUGUUAAAUCAGAGGUGGACACACGGAGGCAAGGCCAGCAGCUGCAGGACCUCAAGACACCUGGGCAGACACUGCAAGAUGAGCUUAGAAAAUGAAGACAAGCGAGCUCGCACCCGAUCCAAGGCCCUGCGAGGACCCCCAGAGACCACAGCUGCAGACCUCAGCUGCCCCACCCCAGGAUGCACAGGCUCAGGGCACGUCCGGGGCAAGUACUCCAGGCACCGAAGUUUACAGAGCUGCCCCCUGGCCAAGAAGAGGAAGCUGGAGGGCGCUGAGGCUGAGCACCUGGUGUCCAAGAGGAAGUCACACCCCCUGAAGCUGGCUCUGGACGAGGGCUAUGGUGUGGACAGCGACGGCAGUGAGGACACUGAGGUGAAGGACGCCUCUGUUUCGGAUGAAUCGGAAGGAACUCUGGAGGGGGCCGAGGCUGAGACGUCAGGACAGGACGAGAUUCAUCGCCCCGAGACAGCUGAAGGAAGGAGCCCCGUCAAGUCCCAUUUUGGAUCCAACCCCAUCGGCAGCGCCACUGCCUCCUCCAAGGGCAGCUACAGCAGCUACCAGGGAAUCAUCGCAACUUCUCUCCUGAACUUGGGUCAAAUUGCUGAAGAGACCCUGGUGGAAGAGGACUUGGGCCAGGCGGCCAAGCCAGGUCCUGGCAUUGUGCACCUGCUUCAGGAGGCUGCAGAGGGAGCUGCCAGCGAGGAGGGUGAAAAGGGCCUCUUCAUCCAGCCAGAGGAUGCCGAGGAGGUCGUCGAAGUCACCACCGAGCGCUCCCAGGACCUGUGUCCCCAGUCCCUGGAGGAUGCAGCCAGUGAGGAGUCCAGCAAGCAGAAAGGCAUCCUGAGUCACGAAGAGGAGGACGAGGAGGAGGAGGAGGAGGAAGAGGAGGAGGAGGAGGAUGAAGAAGAGGAAGAGGAAGAGGAGGAGGAAGAGGAAGAGGAGGAGGAGGAAGAGGAAGAGGAGGAGGAAGAGGAAGAGGAAGAGGAGGAGGAGGAGGCAGCUCCUGAUGUGAUCUUUCAGGAAGACACCUCUCACACCUCUGCCCAGAAGGCCCCUGAGCUCCGGGGCCCAGAAUCACCCAGUCCCAAGCCUGAGUACUCUGUUAUUGUGGAGGUCCGCUCGGAUGAUGACAAGGACGAGGACACCCACUCCCGGAAGUCAACAGUCACUGACGAGUCGGAGAUGCAGGACAUGAUGACCCGGGGAAACCUGGGCCUCCUGGAGCAGGCCAUCGCCCUGAAGGCUGAACAGGUGCGCACAGUCUGCGAGCCGGGCUGCCCGCCUGCCGAGCAGAGCCAGCUGGGCCUGGGAGAGCCAGGGAAGGCAGCAAAGCCCCUGGACACUGUGCGGAAGAGUUACUACAGUAAAGAUCCUUCAAGAGCUGAGAAGCGUGAGAUCAAGUGUCCAACACCAGGCUGUGAUGGCACUGGCCACGUUACCGGGUUGUACCCUCACCACCGCAGCCUUUCUGGCUGUCCCCACAAGGAUAGGAUCCCCCCAGAGAUCUUAGCCAUGCAUGAGAACGUGCUGAAGUGCCCCACUCCUGGCUGCACAGGCCAGGGUCACGUGAACAGCAACCGCAACACGCACAGAAGUUUGUCUGGGUGUCCCAUUGCUGCCGCCGAAAAAUUAGCCAAAUCCCAUGAGAAGCAGCAGCCGCAGACAGGAGAUCCUUCCAAGAGUAGCUCCAAUUCCGAUCGGAUCCUCAGGCCCAUGUGCUUCGUGAAGCAGCUCGAGGUCCCUCCAUAUGGGAGCUACCGGCCCAACGUGGCCCCCGCCACACCCAGGGCCAACUUGGCCAAGGAGCUGGAGAAGUUCUCCAAGGUCACCUUUGACUACGCAAGUUUCGAUGCUCAGGUUUUUGGCAAACGCAUGCUUGCCCCAAAGAUUCAGACCAGCGAAACCUCACCUAAAGCCUUUCAAUGCUUUGACUACUCGCAGGACGCCGAGGCUGCACACAUGGCUGCCACUGCCAUCCUGAACCUCUCCACGCGCUGCUGGGAGAUGCCUGAGAACCUCAGCACGAAGCCACAGGACCUCCCCAGCAAGUCUGUGGAUAUCGAGGUAGACGAAAAUGGAACCCUGGACUUGAGCAUGCACAAACACCGCAAACGAGAAAAUGCUUUCCCCAGCAGCAGCAGCUGCAGCAGCAGCCCCGGUGUGAAGUCUCCCGACGCCUCCCAGCGCCACAGCAGCACCAGCGCCCCCAGCAGCUCCAUGACCUCUCCCCAGUCCAGCCAGGCCUCCCGCCAGGACGAGUGGGACCGGCCCCUGGACUACACCAAGCCUAGCCGCCUGAGAGAGGAGGAACCUGAGGAGUCAGAGCCAGCAGCCCAUUCUUUUGCUUCUUCUGAAGCAGAUGACCAGGAAGUGUCGGAAGAGAAUUUUGAGGAGCGGAAGUAUCCGGGGGAAGUCACCCUGACCAACUUUAAGCUGAAGUUUCUCUCCAAGGACAUAAAGAAGGAGCUGCUCACCUGUCCCACCCCUGGCUGUGACGGCAGCGGCCACAUCACCGGGAACUACGCCUCCCACCGCAGCCUCUCUGGUUGCCCUCUUGCUGACAAGAGCCUCAGAAACCUCAUGGCUGCCCACUCUGCUGACCUCAAGUGCCCCACGCCCGGCUGUGACGGCUCUGGCCACAUCACAGGGAACUACGCUUCACACCGGAGCUUGUCCGGCUGCCCUCGUGCAAAGAAAAGUGGAGUCAAGGUGGCACCCACCAAGGACGACAAGGAGGACCCCGAGCUGAUGAAGUGCCCAGUUCCAGGCUGUGUGGGGCUCGGUCACAUCAGCGGGAAAUACGCCUCUCACAGGAGCGCAUCCGGCUGCCCACUGGCCGCCCGCAGGCAGAAGGAAGGGUCCCUCAAUGGCUCGUCAUUCUCCUGGAAGUCCCUGAAGAAUGAAGGACCGACCUGCCCCACCCCGGGCUGUGACGGCUCUGGCCACGCCAAUGGGAGUUUCCUCACCCACCGGAGUUUGUCAGGCUGUCCCAGAGCAACCUUUGCUGGAAAGAAGGGAAAACUGUCAGGGGAUGAGGUCCUCAGUCCAAAGUUCAAGACUAGCGACGUGUUGGAGAAUGAUGAGGAGAUCAAGCAGCUGAACCAGGAGAUCCGAGACCUGAACGAGUCCAACUCGGAGAUGGAGGCUGCCAUGGUGCAGCUGCAGUCCCAGAUCUCCUCCAUGGAGAAGAACCUGAAGAACAUCGAGGAGGAGAACAAGCUCAUUGAGGAGCAGAAUGAAGCCCUGUUUCUGGAGCUGUCCGGCCUGAGCCAGGCCCUCAUCCAAAGUCUCGCCAAUAUCCGCCUUCCGCACAUGGAGCCAAUAUGCGAACAGAAUUUCGAUGCCUAUGUGAGCACCCUCACCGACAUGUACUCCAACCAGGACCCGGAGAACAAGGACCUCCUGGAGAGCAUCAAGCAGGCUGUGAGGGGCAUCCAGGUCUAGGCCGUGUGGUACCCAGAAGUGUCCCAGCCCACCACACCGUUUACCUCCCUCGCCCUGCCCCGCACCGUGGGGAUGCCCAACUCACAGUGACUUCCCGUUUGGGGCCCGGUGUGGCCGCGGGCGGGUUUAUCCAAAGGGAUGGCUGGAAAUUGGCCGCUCCCACGAGGCUCCCUCCAGGCUUGGGGCCGUGGUGGCCCUAUCUGUGUGCAUAGGGGCACUGAAGAAUUACAAAGUGAUUUAUUUUUGUUUUCUGAAAGAAAUCUGAAGAGCAGCUCAAAGUCUCCAGUGGAAGCUCAUGGACAAGGUUCUCAGGGAAGUUUUGGAGUUUGCAACCACAGUAUUCCUUUGUCUGUCGAGGCUGGGAGGGUAGCCGUGAGCGUGGUGGGUGGGUGGUGUGAGUGGCAUCUUGGCCUGGAGGACACGCCUGGGGCAGCGUGUCUGUGCUCAGUGAGGGCCGAUGAAGAAAGUGCGUUUUCUGUUUUCAUUUAAUUCAGUUUUGUGUUAAGGGUGGAACAAAGCUCUGUUCUAGAGGGAAAGUUAGGAAUAGGCCUCCCAGAGGAUACUCCAGACAGUUGACAAGCAUCGCAGCCCCUGUCAGGUCAAGGAAUUUUAACCUGGGAGACUCCUGAAAAUCAGCCUAAUGUCUGGGGGCAGCUGGCGCUGAGGCUGUGCAGAUGUGUAUGGCCUUGGGUCACAGCUCCCUACUGGGGCUGCAGCCUUUAGACCCUGGGUCUGGGAUCCACGUCUAGGGACCACUCUGGCUUCUGUGCAUCCACCCAGGCCCCCGACCCAUCACUGCCACAUUCUCCGGGUCAUGGCCGAGCUUGACCUCUGCAUCCAUGGUGACGGAGGUGGCAAUGACAUCAUCAAGGUCAGAGGGUAAAUUCCUAACAGGAGACCACAAAGGUUUCACUUCUUUUAGAUCCAUCCAAUAUGCGAAAAAAGGGUACAUUUUAAUUUAAUGUGUUAAAAACACAAUGUCCCUACCGUGUAAAUAGAAUCCAAGUCAAUUGUGACUGCAAUUCCAAGUUAGUAUUUAAAAAUAGAGAAAUUGCACUUCCUGGAAAAAAUUAAAAAGUAGUUAGUUUAAUUAUUCUGUAAAUUAUUUAAUUUUGUCAAGAUGUAAGUAUUUAUAUUCACAGCCUCUUAUGUUAACGUUUGCUAUUUAUUUAACAUUUUUAUUUAUUAAUUUUAUACUAUUUCAACUAGACCCCACACCAGGGCACCCUAAGAGGGGAAAAAAGUGAAUUCAAAGCAAAAAUAACUAUUUGACUAUAAUAUAGGCCACAAAAAAUCUUGAUAUAACUCCUAGUUAUAAUUUUGAUGCAACCAAGUUAUUUUUUAUAUAUUUUGUUAUUUAUUCUUUUAAUAAUGGAAUUUUUUUAAAAAGUAUUUUGUAACUGAGGAAUUUUGAUAAUUUGGGGAUUUUGUUUUCCCUUGGUCUAAUGGAGAGAAAGACAUUUUGGUUUUCUUUUUCCAUUUUGGGUUCCUUUUGUUUCAGGCACGGAUAACAGCAAAUGGAAUUCUGUAUUUAUUAUUAUUUAAGUGUAGCGCAGAUGUGUGUGCUUGGGCGUGUUUCUCGUGUCGCGUUUGCGUGUCGGCUCUUGCGGUGGAGUCCUGUUGCUGUGAGGGAGUGCUGGCCGCAGGCAGCCUCGAGUCACCGCCAGGCUCACAGGCUGUGCCACCCGUCCCUCCGACAGCUCCAAUACUGUGACCCUCCUUCCUCAGGAAGCGCGUUGAACCCACAGCACUCCGUGGUGUGUUUGCAGGGUGAUUUCCUAAUAAAAGUCCACUCUGACUGUGAA